CCUGGCAGUGGGGCUGGAUACUGGCCUGCCUCCCACCAGAGUCCCCCCAGCUCCUCCCUGCUGUGGGCUGGCCUGGGAGGAAGGGGGUGGGGUGCACUUACAUUUGCAGGUCUUUCCAGCCCCUGGGGCAGCCUGAUUAACCAGCUUCUCCAGGGCCAAGCUGUUGGGGGUGAGGUGCAGCCCGAAGCAGCCAGACCAGCCCCUGAGCCUCCCGGGUGCUGGCAGCUGUCAUGGGGCUACCCUGGGGGCAGCCUCACCUAGGGCUGCAGAUGCUCCUCCUGGCAUUGAACUGUCUCCGGCCCAGCCUGAGCCUGGGUGAGUGGGGGUCCUGGAUGGACGCGUCCAGCCAGACCCAAGGGGCUGGGGGCCCUGCUGGAGUGAUUGGACCCUGGGCGCCCGCCCCCCUCCGAUUGGGAGAGGCAGCCCCAGGGACCCCCACGCCCGUCUCCGUGGCUCACCUUUUGUCCCCCGUGGCCACAGAGCUGGUGCCCUACACACCACAGAUAACAGCUUGGGACCUGGAAGGGAAGGUCACAGCCACCACCUUCUCCCUGGAGCAGCCGCGCUGUGUCUUCGAUGGGCUUGCCAGCGCCAGCGAUACCGUCUGGCUCGUGGUGGCCUUCAGCAAUGCCUCCAGGGGCUUCCAGAACCCGGAGACACUGGCUGACAUUCCGGCCUCCCCACAGCUGCUGACCGAUGGCCACUACAUGACGCUGCCCCUGUCUCCGGACCAGCUGCCCUGUGGCGACCCCAUGGCGGGCAGCGGAGGCGCCCCCGUGCUGCGGGUGGGCCAUGACCACGGCUGCCACCAGCAGCCCUUCUGCAACGCGCCCCUCCCUGGCCCUGGACCCUAUCGGGAAGACCCCCGGAUCCAUCGACACCUGGCCAGGGCGGCGAAGUGGCAGCAUGAUCGUCAUUACCUCCAUCCUCUCUUCUCUGGCCGGCCUCCUACUCUUGGCCUUCUUGGCAGCCUCUACCAUGCGCUUCUCCAGCCUGUGGUGGCCGGAGGAGGCCCCGGAGCAGCUGCGGAUCGGCUCCUUCAUGGGCAAGCGCUACAUGACCCACCACAUCCCACCCAGCGAGGCCGCCACACUGCCGGUGGGCUGCAAGCCUGGCCUGGACCCCCUCCCCAGCCUCAGCCCCUAGCCUGGCCUCUUUGCAUGGGGCUGGGGGAGAUGGGGCGCCGGGAGUGAGUGCAUGGUGCUUUGUCCCAGCUCCUGCACCCACAGGCCCCCUCAGGGCUCCUUGCCUUUCCCCCCCACCAGCACACCCCGUACCCUGCCUGGAAUCCCAGCACCAGCCCCCCUGCCUCUCCUCUGCCUUUCUGGUUUCUCUCCCUCUCCAAGCAUCUGUAAGUUGCACUCAGGAGGGUUUAGGGGAGGGCCAUGGGCAGGCUGGUCUCGUGAUAGUGAGUGAGUGCUCAUGGGAUCUGGUUGUUUAGAAGCAUGCAGCACCUCCUGCUUCACUCUCUCUGUCUCUCCUGCUCCACCAUGGCCAGAAACGUGCCUGCUUCCCCUUCGCCUUCUGCCGUGAUUGUCAGUUUCUUGAGGGCUCCCCAGCCAUGCUUCCUGUACAGCCUGCAAAACUGUGAGUCAAUUAAACCUCUUUUCUUCAUAAA